CGAGGGCCACUGCUCCCUGGACUUCUGUCGGAACCGGACGCAGUGGGAGGGGUCGCAGGGCGCCCGCGGGGCAGGAAGGAUGCGGGCCGCGCCCACCUCUGAGUCCCCUCUGCCAGCCUCUUCCUCUGGCCCCAGGAGACCUGAGGCUCAGAACCUACACAACACCAGGUUAAGAAGAGGGGCCUGGUGGCCUUUCCUCACCCAGCCGCCCUCCUUCGCCCCGGCCCCCAGCUAGCCCCCACACAAUGAACAGCUUGUUGAGAAUUUGCAUUUUAUGAAAAUCAUGUUGAAAGACAAAGGGGUCUCUCUGUGCUGCCCAGUCCUUCCUCCCUGGCCGUUUGGGAACUGUCCCCACCCCUGAGGCCAAUCUGGUUCUGAACCUUCUCUUCCUUGCCUUGGGCAGCUUUGGGGGAGGGUUAGCAAAGGCACAGAACAGAAAGGCCCUGGGCUGUGCAGGCUCCAAAGAAAAGGGCUGCUCUGGGACUGGACCUCCUCCCAGGACCAAAAAGUUAGGGAGGGUGAGAGACUACUUUAGUUUAUCAAGGACCCUGAAGAGACAGGAACCUUCAUCUCUCAUCCUUCCUCCACACCCCCCACCACCACCCCUAAAGAACUCCCAGUCUCGGUCCUUUAGUGAGACUUGCUGACAAGUUUGACAUCUAAGAUGUUUUGUCCCAGAAAGCACAAAAUAUAUGGCAAUGGAGAGAGAGACCCAGGUAUAGCUGGGCACAGCUGGUCACCUGCAGCUGGGAUCCACAACUGGUCCUUGAAACGGCCUGUACCUUAGGAGACCUGGCACCUCUGACCCCACAUUCUGGCUGGGAUUGCCAGCCCUUCGGGACAGGGUCCCUGACCCCAGCCCUCCCAAGCCACUGUCUGUAGCUGAGAAAUUAGAUGGAGAGACCCAACUGGCAGAAGGUCCUCGGAGCACCUUGAUAGGGCUCAGGAUUCCGCUGGAAGAAUCUCAGCCAGAGUCCUGAACAGCAGCGGAAAGUGCUGACGUUGGAGAAGGAGGAUAACCAGACCUUCGGCUUUGAGAUCCAGACUUAUGGCCUUCACCACCGGGAGGAGCAGCGUGUGGAAAUGGUGACCUUUGUCUGCCGAGUUCAUGAGUCUAGCCCUGCCCAGCUGGCUGGGCUCACACCAGGGGACACCAUCGCCAGCGUCAAUGGCCUGAAUGUGGAAGGCAUCCGGCAUCGAGAGAUUGUGGACAUCAUUAAGGCGUCAGGCAAUGUUCUCAGACUGGAAACUCUAUAUGGGACAUCAAUUCGGAAGGCAGAACUGGAGGCUCGUCUGCAGUACCUGAAGCAAACCCUGUAUGAGAAGUGGGGAGAGUACAGGUCCCUAAUGGUGCAGGAGCAGCGGCUGGUGCAUGGCCUGGUGGUGAAGGACCCCAGCAUCUACGACACGCUGGAGUCGGUGCGCUCCUGCCUCUACGGCGCGGGCCUGCUCCCGGGCUCGCUGCCCUUCGGGCCUCUGCUCGCCGUGCCCGGGCGUCCCCGCGGAGGCGCCCGACGGGCCAGGGGCGACGCCGACGACGCCGUCUACCACACGUGCUUCUUCGGGGACUCCGAGCCGCCGGCGCUGCCGCCCCCGCCGCCCCCGGCCCGCGCCUUCGGCCCGGGCCCCGCCGAGACCCCUGCCGUGGGGCCGGGCCCUGGGCCGCGGGCCGCGCUGAGCCGCAGCGCCAGUGUGCGGUGCGCGGGCCCUGGCGGGGGCGGAGGCGGGGGCGCGCCGGGCGCGCUCUGGACUGAGGCUCGCGAGCAGGCCCUAUGCGGCCCCGGCCUGCGCAAAACCAAGUACCGCAGCUUCCGCCGGCGGCUGCUCAAGUUCAUCCCCGGACUCAACCGCUCCCUGGAGGAGGAGGAGAGCCAGCUGUAGGGGCGGGGGCGGGCAGGGAGGUAUUUAUUUAUUUAUUCGCAACAGCCAGCGCUAAAAGAGGGGGAGGCCGAGCCAAGAGGACCCCAGGAGCCCAGAGCAGCGGGAGAGGGUCCUUCCUAGCCUCGGCCCGCCGGGUCGGUUCCUGGCUGGUGUCUGCUGAGGGAGUGGGGGGCCCAGCCCCUUCUCUUCUCCCCCGCCAAACCACAGUGGGAGCUGGGGCAGGGGGAGAGCCAGGCAAUCGGGGGCCAAAGAUGGGGGUGCUCGCCUACAGUCUGCAUCUGUAGUGCCUUGUGGGGUAUCCAGGAACACCCUCCCAGCAGGGGAUGGGAACCCUGUCCCAUGAAGCCCUCUCCUCAGCUUUACUUGCUCCCCCGCCCUUAGCCUUGGGGAGAAAUGGCCCGUGGUGGGCUGACCCCCCACCCUCCACACACACAGUUCCAUGACCCAGCGGGCCCCCAGGGGCAUCAGGUGCUGGUCCUCCUCCCUCCUGGCCUCGACCCCUAAGGGCUUCGCCCCUCCCAGGGGCCUGUAACUAAGUCGGGUCCUGCCAGGCAGGGGGCCUGUGUUCUGUGCCCCUUGGGAGACAGGAACUGGCGAGUUCAGGUGGGGUGGGGACAGCACAGACUGUUCCACCGUUGUGCAUAUUGUUGCUUCUGAACCACAAACUGUAUAAAUGGAUGGUUUUUUGCA